AAGUCGGUGCCGCUGCCGUCUCUGCGUUCGCCAUGCGUCCCGGGGCGCCAGGGCCACUCUGGCCUCUGCCCUGGGGGGCCCUGGCUUGGGCCGUGGGCUUCGUGAGCUCCAUGGGCUCGGGGAACCCCGCGCCCGGUGGUGUUUGCUGGCUCCAGCAGGGCCAGGAGGCCACCUGCAGCCUGGUGCUCCAGACUGAUGUCACCCGGGCCGAGUGCUGUGCCUCCGGCAACAUUGACACCGCCUGGUCCAACCUCACCCACCCGGGGAACAAGAUCAACCUCCUCGGCUUCUUGGGCCUUGUCCACUGCCUUCCCUGCAAAGAUUCGUGCGACGGCGUGGAGUGCGGCCCGGGCAAGGCGUGCCGCAUGCUGGGGGGCCGCCCGCGCUGCGAGUGCGCGCCCGACUGCUCGGGGCUCCCGGCGCGGCUGCAGGUCUGCGGCUCAGACGGCGCCACCUACCGCGACGAGUGCGAGCUGCGCGCCGCGCGCUGCCGCGGCCACCCGGACCUGAGCGUCAUGUACCGGGGCCGCUGCCGCAAGUCCUGUGAGCACGUGGUGUGCCCGCGGCCACAGUCGUGCGUCGUGGACCAGACGGGCAGCGCCCACUGCGUGGUGUGUCGAGCGGCGCCCUGCCCUGUGCCCUCCAGCCCCGGCCAGGAGCUUUGCGGCAACAACAACGUCACCUACAUCUCCUCGUGCCACAUGCGCCAGGCCACCUGCUUCCUGGGCCGCUCCAUCGGCGUGCGCCACGCGGGCAGCUGCGCAGGCACCCCUGAGGAGCCGCCAGGUGGUGAGUCUGCAGAAGAGGAAGAGAACUUCGUGUGAGCCUGCAGGACAGGCCUGGGCCUGGUGCCCGAGGCCCCCCAUCAUCCCCUGUUAUUUAUUGCCACAGCAGAGUCUAAUUUAUAUGCCACGGACACUCCUUAGAGCCCGGAUUCGGACCACUUGGGGAUCCCAGAACCUCCCUGACGAUAUCCUGGAAGGACUGAGGAAGGGAGGCCUGGGGGCCGGCUGGUGGGUGGGAUAGACCUGCGUUCCGGACACUGAGCGCCUGAUUUAGGGCCCUUCUCUAGGAUGCCCCAGCCCCUACCCUAAGACCUAUUGCCGGGGAGGAUUCCACACUUCCGCUCCUUUGGGGAUAAACCUAUUAAUUAUUGCUACUAUCAAGAGGGCUGGGCAUUCUCUGCUGGUAAUUCCUGAAGAGGCAUGACUGCUUUUCUCAGCCCCAAGCCUCUAGUCUGGGUGUGUACGGAGGGUCUAGCCUGGGUGUGUACGGAGGGUCUAGCCUGGGUGAGUACGGAGGGUCUAGCCUGGGUGAGUACGGAGGGUCUAGCCUGGGUGAGUACGGAGGGUCUAGCCUGGGUGUGUAUGGAGGAUCUAGCCUGGGUGAGUAUGGAGGGUCUAGCCUGGGUGAGUAUGGAGGGUCUAGCCUGGGUGUGUAUGGAGGGUCUAGCCUGGGUGAGUAUGGAGGGUCUAGCCUGGGUGUGUAUGGAGGGUCUAGCCUGGGUGAGUAUGGAGGGUCUAGCCUGGGUGUGUACGGAGGGUCUAGUCUGAGUGCGUGUGGGGACCUCAGAACACUGUGACCUUAGCCCAGCAAGCCAGGCCCUUCAUGAAGGCCAAGAAGGCUGCCACCAUUCCCUGCCAGCCCAAGAACUCCAGCUUCCCCACUGCCUCUGUGUGCCCCUUUGCGUCCUGUGAAGGCCAUUGAGAAAUGCCCAGUGUGCCCCCUGGGAAAGGGCACGGCCUGUGCUCCUGACACGGGCUGUGCUUGGCCACAGAACCACCCAGCGUCUCCCCUGCUGCUGUCCACGUCAGUUCAUGAGGCAACGUCGCGUGGUCUCAGACGUGGAGCAGCCAGCGGCAGCUCAGAGCAGGGCACUGUGUCCGGCGGAGCCAAGUCCACUCUGGGGGAGCUCUGGCGGGGACCACGGGCCACUGCUCACCCACUGGCCCCGAGGGGGGUGUAGACGCCAAGACUCACGCAUGUGUGACAUCCGGAGUCCUGGAGCCGGGUGUCCCAGUGGCACCACUAGGUGCCUGCUGCCUCCACAGUGGGGUUCACACCCAGGGCUCCUUGGUCCCCCACAACCUGCCCCGGCCAGGCCUGCAGACCCAGACUCCAGCCAGACCUGCCUCACCCACCAAUGCAGCCGGGGCUGGCGACACCAGCCAGGUGCUGGUCUUGGGCCAGUUCUCCCACGACGGCUCACCCUCCCCUCCAUCUGCGUUGAUGCUCAGAAUCGCCUACCUGUGCCUGCGUGUAAACCACAGCCUCAGACCAGCUAUGGGGAGAGGACAACACGGAGGAUAUCCAGCUUCCCCGGUCUGGGGUGAGGAAUGUGGGGAGCUUGGGCAUCCUCCUCCAGCCUCCUCCAGCCCCCAGGCAGUGCCUUACCUGUGGUGCCCAGAAAAGUGCCCCUAGGUUGGUGGGUCUACAGGAGCCUCAGCCAGGCAGCCCACCCCACCCUGGGGCCCUGCCUCACCAAGGAAAUAAAGACUCAA